AUAGAGGGCAUGGACUGUGGAGAGGUGGUGAGCGCAGGGGCUGGUUUGGCCCAGGCAACUCAGCCUCCUUGAGGGGCCCUCAUGGUCUCUCCCAACCCACAUGCCAUGCUGACCGUGGUGGUAGAAGUGGAGUCGGGGAGGGGUUCAGGAACAAAACUUCACCUUUGACAGUCCUGGGCCCUGAUGCUGCUCAGGAGGCAGAGCAGGAGCUGCUGGCACGUGUCCAAUCCACACUGGGCUCUCUGGGCCGAGGGUACAGUGUGGCCCUGUUGCUCCGGGGGAGGGAAACAGAGGCACCCCGACUUGUGCCUCAGCCUGGGCGACAAGAGCAAAAUUCCGUCUCAAAAAAAAAAGGCGUUUUUCGGGAGUCAAGAUGGCCGAAUACGAACAGCUCAGGUCUACAGCUCCCAGCGUGAGCGACGCAGAAGACGGGUGAUUUCUGCAUUUCCAUCUGAGCUGCUGCAGAUGCUGUUUGAAGAAGCUCUGCCCCUCAGCUGCUCUGAUCCUGUGCUUAGCACUCUUAGCCUGGUGCAGUUCAGCCCCAGUGGAAGGACCCAGGACCUGCUCUCUCCAGGGGUGGAGAACCUGUCGGUGCUGGACGUGUCCCCUCUGGGCUUGGUGGUAGAAGAUGCCACUGAAGUGGAGGUGUCUGACUCAAAAGCUGCCUCAGAGCUGUACUUGCAGGCCACCGCAGGUGAAGGCAGGGCCUGCUGUCUGCUCACUCUCACCAUGUCCUGCCCAGGGCCUGACCCUCCUGAGGGGCCCGGGACCCAGCGUGUGUGGCAAGGGGCUCUACGGAUCCUACAGCUCCCAGGAGCCCCAGACUGCCCCCUGCUGCGGGUGUUGGCUGGUGAAGUUGUUGGUGAGGAGGCGGAGGGCUCUUUGCCCUGGAUUGUCUCAUGGCUCUUGGAAGGAAACAACUACAGUGGCCUACUUCUUCGCCUGGACCCCCAAGGUGGCCAGGGGGAGAGUGUGGAGUUCUUUGGGAAGCUCUGAGAUCUGUCCUUAGGCCUGCCUCACCCAUCACGCAACCGGCCUCAGCCCCAACCUCAGCCCAGAGAGAGCGUCUGACCCUCCAAGAGGGCCCCAGAGUGCCUAGGCUGACAGAGACUGGAGAGGCAAAGUAAGGUCAAUAGUGAAAGUAACCCCUCACCCUUCAGAGACCUUAAACCACUUACCAAGCAUUUUUGCACAAAUGCCUUUGAUUCUUACCACAACCCCAUGAGGCAGAUAUAAUUUACAAAUAAGGAAAGAGAGGCAGGCCUAAUUUAUAGAUGAGAAUAGAGAGGAUAAGAGAAGAGAAGGGAGUCUCCUAUUUUCAUACACCCAUUAAAAAUCAAGCCUCAGCUGGGUGUGGUGGCUCAUGCCUGCAAUCCCAGCAUUUUGGGAGGCUGAGGUGGGCAGAUCACCUGAGGUCAGGAGUUCAGGACUAGCCUGGCCAACAUGGUGAAACUCCAUCUCUACUAAAAAUACAAAAAUUAGCUGGGCAUGGUGGCAGGUGCCUGUAGUCCCAGCUACUUGGGAGGCUGAGGCAUGAGAACUGCUUGAACCUGGGAGGCAGAGGUUGCAGUGAGCCAAGAUCGUGCUACUGCCCUCUAGCCUGGGCGACAGAGUGAGACUCCAUCUCAAAAAAAUAAAAAAUAAAAAAACAAA